CCGGCCGGGCCGAGAGGUGGUUACAUUCGUUGAAGGACACCAGCUGCGGAAUUUGCGGCUUUGGCAGCUGUUUGUUCCCACCGAGCUGUGCUUUAGGAAGCUGGCCAGCCGGGCCUCCUUUAGGUGCGCUGCAGCCUUUUUCAAAGCGAGUGAAUGUGGCCCGGCCCCUACAGUUCGCCAGGCCCGCUGUAAAAGGGUUAGAUUUCAGUCUAUAGACGAUCAGUGGGAAGGCCUUUCCUAGGAGGUAACCAGAACAGAGAGCUGUAAACUCCGUGAAUGCAAGAGGCUGCUUCUGUUACCUGAGUGGUUCUCACUCAUCUUUGCCUUCCUUACCUCGUGAUCUCACCAUUCCAGACCCAGCUGAGUCACUGUCACUGCCUACCAAUCUCGACCGGACCUCGACCGGCUCGUCUGUGUUGCCAAUCGACUCGGCGUGGCGUCGGUCGUGGUAGAUAGGCGGUCAUGCAUACGAAUUUUCAGCUCUUGUUCUGGUGACCUUUUGAAUACGUCUUGUCUAUAAAAGAAAUUCAUGCCUUUGUAAAAUACACAGAUUGAAAUCAUGGCAGGUCCAGAAAGUGAUGCGCAAUACCAGUUCACUGGUAUUAAAAAAUAUUUCAACUCUUAUACUCUCACAGGUAGAAUGAACUGUGUACUGGCCACAUAUGGAAGCAUUGCAUUGAUUGUCUUAUAUUUCAAGUUAAGGUCCAAAAAAACUCCAGCUGUGAAAGCAACAUAAAUGGAUUUUAAACUGUCUACGGUUCUUAACCUCAUCUGUUAAGUUCCCAUGCCUGGAGAAGCUAAUGCCAACUCAUCAUGUGAUAAUUCAAUUUGUACAAUAAAUUAUGAACCUGGAAAA